GAAAAAUAUUAUCUCCAAGUAUUUAUGUCCUUUUUAGUCUAUAACUGGGAUCUGUUAGAAAUUGAGGAGGAAAUAAAUUUAUGCCUUAAUAGUUUUAGUAUUAGAGGAUAUGGUCUUACAGCAUGUAAUUAACAAAAAUCAAUACAGAAAAGGGAAGAGAGGAAAGAGAUUUCAGAAACACACACACAAACACACACACACACACACACACACACACACACACACACGUAUUUAGGAAGCACAGGUAAAGACGAAAAUAUGUUUCUCCAACAGUCCCAGUCUUCCGUGUUAUUAGAAUAUUUCCUUUUCUGUUACCUACUGUCAGCAUAUUUAAGAUUGGUUUUAACUGAUAUUUCAUUUCCUUAAAUCAGACCAGCCUUGCAGCUGUUUAAGGUCCUAAGGCAUCUAGGGUGUGACUUCCCUCUCCCUUUUCUCUCUGGGAUACAUACGCAAGCACACUGGUCUGAAGGCUGAAGAGAAGGGUAAAGUGGAAGCAUUGGUCUUGCUGUUUCAGAGGUGGCAGAGGCUGAAGAAAAUUCAUUUGGGAUGCCAUCACUGAAAUGGAUGAACAUAAUAGGCCCAUUCACACAUACCAGGUAUGUAAUGUAAUGGAACCAAACCAAAACAACUGGCUUCGUACAAACUGGAUCUCCCGUGAUGCAGCUCAGAAAAUUUAUGUGGAAAUGAAAUUCACACUAAGGGAUUGUAACAGCAUCCCAUGGGUCUUGGGGACUUGCAAAGAAACAUUUAAUCUGUUUUAUAUGGAAUCAGAUGAGUCCCACGGAAUUAAAUUCAAGCCAAACCAGUAUACAAAGAUCGACACAAUUGCUGCUGAUGAGAGUUUUACCCAGAUGGAUUUGGGUGAUCGCAUCCUCAAACUCAACACUGAAAUUCGUGAGGUGGGGCCUAUAGAAAGGAAAGGAUUUUAUCUGGCUUUUCAAGACAUUGGGGCGUGCAUUGCCCUGGUUUCAGUCCGUGUUUUCUACAAGAAAUGCCCCUUCACUGUUCGUAACUUGGCCAUGUUUCCUGAUACCAUUCCAAGGGUUGAUUCCUCCUCUUUGGUUGAAGUACGGGGUUCUUGUGUGAAGAGUGCUGAAGAGCGUGACACUCCUAAACUGUAUUGUGGAGCUGAUGGAGAUUGGCUGGUUCCUCUUGGAAGGUGCAUCUGCAGUACAGGAUAUGAAGAAAUUGAGGGUUCUUGCCAUGCUUGCAGACCAGGAUUCUAUAAAGCUUUUGCUGGGAACACAAAAUGUUCUAAAUGUCCUCCACACAGUUUAACAUACAUGGAAGCAACUUCUGUCUGUCAGUGUGAAAAGGGUUAUUUCCGAGCUGAAAAAGACCCACCUUCUAUGGCAUGUACCAGGCCACCUUCAGCUCCUAGGAAUGUGGUUUUUAACAUCAAUGAAACAGCCCUUAUUUUGGAAUGGAGCCCACCAAGUGACACAGGAGGGAGAAAAGAUCUCACAUACAGUGUAAUCUGUAAGAAAUGUGGCUUAGACACCAGCCAGUGUGAGGACUGUGGUGGAGGACUCCGCUUCAUCCCAAGACAUACAGGCCUGAUCAACAAUUCCGUGAUAGUACUUGACUUUGUGUCUCACGUGAAUUACACCUUUGAAAUAGAAGCAAUGAAUGGAGUUUCUGAGUUGAGUUUUUCUCCCAAGCCAUUCACAGCUAUUACAGUGACCACGGAUCAAGAUGCACCUUCCCUGAUAGGUGUGGUAAGGAAGGACUGGGCAUCCCAAAAUAGCAUUGCCCUAUCAUGGCAAGCACCUGCUUUUUCCAAUGGAGCCAUUCUGGACUACGAGAUCAAGUACUAUGAGAAAGUCUACCCACGGAUAGCGCCGGCAUUUUGGCACUACCUGCGGGUAGAAGAACAUGAGCAGCUGACCUACUCUUCCACAAGGUCCAAAGCCCCCAGUGUCAUCAUCACAGGUCUUAAGCCAGCCACCAAAUAUGUAUUUCACAUCCGAGUGAGAACUGCGACAGGAUACAGUGGCUACAGUCAGAAAUUUGAAUUUGAAACAGGAGAUGAAACUUCUGACAUGGCAGCAGAACAAGGACAGAUUCUCGUGAUAGCCACCGCCGCUGUUGGCGGAUUCACUCUCCUCGUCAUCCUCACUUUAUUCUUCUUGAUCACUGGGAGAUGUCAGUGGUACAUAAAAGCCAAGAUGAAGUCAGAAGAGAAGAGAAGAAACCACUUACAGAAUGGGCAUUUGCGCUUCCCGGGAAUUAAAACUUACAUUGAUCCAGAUACAUAUGAAGACCCAUCCCUAGCAGUCCAUGAAUUUGCAAAGGAGAUUGAUCCCUCAAGAAUUCGUAUUGAGAGAGUCAUUGGGGCAGGUGAAUUUGGAGAAGUCUGUAGUGGGCGUUUGAAGACACCAGGGAAAAGAGAGAUCCCAGUUGCCAUUAAAACUUUGAAAGGUGGCCACAUGGAUCGGCAAAGAAGAGAUUUUCUAAGAGAAGCUAGUAUCAUGGGCCAGUUUGACCAUCCAAACAUCAUUCGCCUAGAAGGGGUUGUCACCAAAAGAUCCUUCCCGGCCAUUGGGGUGGAGGCGUUUUGCCCCAGCUUCCUGAGGGCAGGGUUUUUAAAUAGCAUCCAGGCCCCGCAUCCAGUGCCAGGGGGAGGAUCUUUGCCCCCCAGGAUUCCUGCUGGCAGACCAGUAAUGAUUGUGGUGGAAUAUAUGGAGAAUGGAUCCCUAGACUCCUUUUUGCGGAAGCAUGAUGGCCACUUCACAGUCAUCCAGUUGGUCGGAAUGCUCCGAGGCAUUGCAUCAGGCAUGAAGUAUCUUUCUGAUAUGGGUUAUGUUCAUCGAGACCUAGCGGCUCGGAAUAUACUGGUCAAUAGCAACUUAGUAUGCAAAGUUUCUGAUUUUGGUCUCUCCAGAGUGCUGGAAGAUGAUCCAGAAGCUGCUUAUACAACAACUGGUGGAAAAAUCCCCAUAAGGUGGACAGCCCCAGAAGCCAUCGCCUACAGAAAAUUCUCCUCAGCAAGCGAUGCAUGGAGCUAUGGCAUUGUCAUGUGGGAGGUCAUGUCCUAUGGAGAGAGACCUUAUUGGGAAAUGUCUAACCAAGAUGUCAUUCUGUCCAUUGAAGAAGGGUACAGACUUCCAGCUCCCAUGGGCUGUCCAGCAUCUCUACACCAGCUGAUGCUCCACUGCUGGCAGAAGGAGAGAAAUCACAGACCAAAAUUUACUGACAUUGUCAGCUUCCUUGACAAACUGAUCCGAAAUCCCAGUGCCCUUCACACCCUGGUGGAGGACAUCCUUGUAAUGCCAGAGUCCCCUGGUGAAGUUCCGGAAUAUCCUUUGUUUGUCACAGUUGGUGACUGGCUAGAUUCUAUAAAGAUGGGGCAAUACAAGAAUAACUUCGUGGCAGCAGGGUUUACAACAUUUGACCUGAUUUCAAGAAUGAGCAUUGAUGACAUUAGAAGAAUUGGAGUCAUACUUAUUGGACACCAGAGACGAAUAGUCAGCAGCAUACAGACUUUACGUUUACACAUGAUGCACAUACAGGAGAAGGGAUUUCAUGUAUGAAAGUACCACAAGCACCUGUGUUUUGUGCCUCAGCAUUUCUAAAAUGAACGAUAUCCUCUCUACUACUCUCUCUUCUGAUUCUCCAAACAUCACUUCACAAACUGCAGUCUUCUGUUCAGACUAUAGGCACACACCUUAUGUUUAUGCUUCCAACCAGGAUUUUAAAAUCAUGCUACAUAAAUCCGUUCUGAAUAACCUGCAACUAAAACCCUGGCCCACUGCAGAUUAUUGCUACGCAAUGGUAAAUAACUCAGCAUGGAUGUGUAAUUUUGUAUAAGCCGUAUAUGGGAAGUGUUCACGGACUUAACCUAAAAAAAUUUAUCCAGGUGGGGCUUCCUUAGUGAUGUAUGUAGAGUGUGAUGGUAGAUGAGAAAGAACUAGUUGACCUUUCUUUCAUGUUUUGUGAUCAAGUAGCUUCCAAACUGACAGAAAUGUUUCAUUUUUAGAUAAUUAUAUUCAGCUCUAUUGGUUGUAUUAUUACUUUAUUUUUUAAUACUUUAACUGUUGGUGCCUGAUAUUGUUAGAAUUAUUUGCAGAAAUGACCAGUGAUAUCAUGUAAUGAAUUUUUGUGAGGUAUGACUAUGGUGAGAAGGGGGUUAUUAGGGAGGGAGAAAAAAAUACUGUGUUUAUAAAUCUUCUGAGGCUGGGUUUGUCAAUUUUUUAAAAAUUAACUUUAUAAUGUCAUACAUAUUUCAUAGUAGGUGGUAGUUUAAAGGCUUUUCACCUCUAAUUUUAUUUAUUUAUUUAUUUAUUUUUACUAACCGUAGUAUAUUUCUCUACUACCUUAUGAAGACCGCUCCUGGAAAGACCAAGGGUGACUUCAUUGAUCUAAUGGCUUUCAUAGAGAAAAGCUUGGGAUAAAUCCAUGACUAUUUCCUUUGUGCAUUGUCACAAGUUUGCAAAAGCAAUUAUCAAAGCACUGAGAAAAUUGGUCAUUCUCAGUAGAAUUGCUUUGAAUAAAAUACGUUAGAUUAUACCCUUAGAUUUAAUGUAAAAUUAUUAAUUUAAUUUAAACAGAACUUUAUGAUAGAUACAUGGUGGCCCAAGAAAAUAAACAGACUUAGCUGAUCAUUUGGUAUUGGCACAUUUUGCAAGUUGAAGCGUUCUUAUGUUUUCUUUGCAAAAAUAGUUACAUGAACAUGCUGAGCUCUUUUCGAAACCUUCUAAGAAAUAAGUAUGAAUACUCCAAAGAGCAUAUAAACAGAUCUUACACAUGAGCAUAGUGUGUCAACCUGGGUCCAACGUACAGUUACAUAAAAAUGAGAACACAGCUGUGUUGUCAUAAUCUUCUGAGAGGCUUAAAAAACAAAGGUAAAUAUAUAUUUUAAGUGAUUUAAGCUGAGUUGGCUUAUCAAAAUUGUGCUAUAUCUUAUGAACAAAUUAAAUUAUAAAAUCAGCUGCUCCCUGUAAAACUAAAAAAAUGACGACUGUUUUAGGUGAAAGAGUAAGUAAAAUGUGUUGAGAGAAAAAAACAGAGUAGGUUGUCUAAAGAUGCUGAUUUAAUAAAUUAGCUUUUGUUGGAUCUCAGUGAUAAUGGUGCCCUACCUACCCUAAUUCUCAAAUUCCUAUCUAAAUUCAUUUUUUGUCAUAGUAGUGGUUUUUUUUUUUUAAAUAAAGGACCCUGUUUUUGUUUUUUGUUUUUGUUUUUGUUGUUCGUUUGUUUGUUUUUGAGACGGAGGCGUUUUGCUCUUGUUGCCCAGGCUGGAGUGCAAUGGUGAGAUCUUGGCUCACGGCAACCUCUGCCUCCCGGGUUCAAGCGAUUCUCCUGCCUCAGCCACCCGAGUAGCUGGGAUUACAGGCGCCUGCCACCACUCCCGGCUAAUUUUUGUAUUUUUAGUAGAGACGGGGUUUCACCAUGUUGGCCAGGCUGCUCGAACUCCUGACCUCAGAUGAUCUGCCCGCCUCAGCCUCUCAAAGUGCUGAGAUUACAGGCGUGAGCCACCGCGCCUGGCCAUUUUUUUCUUAUAUUUAGAUUUUGUUGAUCGUCCCAUUAUACUAGACCCUUCUACAUAUUUUCUUUUGCUGACUUGUCUCCUGAUUUUUCCCUACCACAGCUUAAUCCUUCUCAUUUCAAAACAAAUGUGUAAAGCAAAGCUAGAAGGAAGAGUCUUUAGAUGUUUCUUAAAAUAUACAAAAAAAGGUAGGGGGUGAUGGGAAAAUCAUCACUUUUCAAGUAAGUGUGCCAGAUAUAGCUAGCCACAUUUUCCAGCCAUCAACCUGCAUGGUUGUGCAUCACUCAUAGACUAUCUGCAGUUUGCUUGAUACAUUUACACAAAUCUGGAUACACUUAGAAGAAAUAUAAAAUUUCCAUAUUUACCUAUCUUCAAAUAUAUAUUAAAUAAGAACAGAUAUAAAACAGAUUAAAUUUAUUAAUCAUAUAUUUAUUUUUAUAAUACAAAAAAGGUAUUUAGGAAAAUAAGGAAUAGAAUAAUAUGGUCUUCCACAGGACUCUGUCGGCACCAUCUGUGUACCUUGAAAUAAAUUCUAUUAAGUUAUUUAAAUUUCUAUGGGAUGAGCAUUCAGUGAUUACAAGAUUAAAGUUGCCUAUUAAGAAUUCUUUCUUUUAAAAUGUCUGAUGAUCCUAUUCUACAUCUGGUUAAUUUGUACUUAUUUUUUCUUUCUCUAACAUCUUUUGAUAGUAUCAUAAAACUACUUUUUGCUUUGUCUCUCAUCCCAUGUCUCCUUCAAAAUUCCUUUUAAAUUAUAAUUUUAUUUUUCAGAAUGGUAAGCAUGAUAAUCUUAAAUGUAACUUUGAACUUCAUUAUGGUUAUGGCAACAUUGAAACAUGUGUGCAAGAUUAAACAGAAACAUUAAAAUAUAAGGAUUUACUAUAAGGAUUUACUGCCUACCAAUCAUGGACCCCAUGAUCCCAGGAAUAUUACAAUAUUCAGGAAUAUAAACAGUUAAAAUGCCAAAUUCAUCUGAAAAUUUUACAUGAAACAUUUUGAGACUUACUAGUGUAAAUUUUAGGUAAUUAAAUCUGUUUAAUAUGCAAAGCAUAAAACUUAAUUAUAAAAAGAAAAUAAGUAACUUCCAUAAAUCACAAGUCUUCAGGAAUAAUCUUUGAUACCUAAAAUAUGCAUAUAGACUCACAUACCUACUUUAUUUUAAAUGUCUUGAUCUAUGCUACUGAGGGGGUGUUUUGGAUUUUAAAACCAGACAGUUAAAAAAUCAUUUUCAUUUUAUUUCUAGAUGGUCAAUUUUGUCUAUGGUGAACUCAUUAUCUCAUAGUAGAAGGCAUAUUUGGAAAAAAUGUGAAAACAAUGUACAAUCAAGGAGAGAGAUAAAGUAUUUAAAUCAUUUUAAAAAGCAAUCAAAUUGCAAAAUUUUGGUGGUUUAACACGAAUCAAGAAUUAUAGCACUUUUGCAAUGAGUUAUAACUGGUGAUAAAUGUUCUACAUUCCAUAUCAAAAUAAGACAUCUUAUUUCACUCUGCAUUGGUCUUUAAAAUCUAUCAAAGUAUAACCUGAAUAAAACUGCCUUCCAGCAACAGCUUUAAAACCUAUCUCAGCCCAUGAAUGGAAAACAAAUCCAAAUCCGAUCCUUGAAAAGCAAAGGCUCUAAAGAAGCUCUUCAGAAGAGACGGUAAAGAAUGAAUUCUUUUACUUAUCACCCAACCACAUUUCUUAAAAAUGUGUUUUGGUGUCUUUUCCUACCAAAUUUCUGCUCUACAAGGCAGUCAGUUAAAUCUCUCAUUUCAUAAUUUUCACUGUGCUAGUUCUUUCUUUUCUCCUCUUUUAAUAAAUUUUCUAAAACUUUCUCAGCCCUGUUUUUAAUUCCCCCAUCCUCUCUCUUUAUUCCUUUCUCAGCUUCUAUCACGCCACACAUUAUCUCAAUCAGCAUAAAAAAGGUAGCACAACAAAUCUAAAAAGAUUGUAUAGACUUUUUUAGAAGAGGCUUGGGGCAGGGGGAUGUUGCAAAAGCUAUAAUAUUUUGGGUUCUAUCACAUAAUUGAGAACAUUUGUACUCACAGAGGAUAUGGGUUCUGGCUUUUCCUUAACUUGAAAUCAAGUUUUUGGAAAGUAAUUUUGAAAUGGAUGAUGAUGAUCCUUUUUAAUUGCUUUAACUAAGGAAGUUUAUUAUUAAUAUUUUAAAAAUUAGUAUUUUAAGAUCAAUAUCUGUUAUUAUAAACUCACAGUUGGUGUCCAUGUCUCUAUAUAUCAAAGAGAUUUGAAGCAUAUGUAUCACUUCUUUUAGUAUGAGCAUCUUAACUUUUCCAAUCUCAAAUUCUGUGAAGUAGAAGAGACUCAUAUUACUUUACAUUCAAUCAACAAAUAUUUUAAUAUUUUUUAAUAUGAAGACUCCAAAAGGUAGAGGAGUACACUGGGUUAAAUGGAUGGUAUUCUUCCACCAGAAUAUAAGAUACUUAAGUCACCUAACUUUUGGUUUUUAUAAGCAACAUUUUCAACAAUUUUUCAAUCUUUAUAAUGUUCCACAAAGACAGUAUAGAUUUUAUCUAGUUCAGCUUAACAAAUAUCUAUGGAAUAUCUCCUAUAUGCACAAAAUUUUACUACAAAGAUACGUUUGGCUGUGCUGUCAUUGCUUUCAAGUAACUCUCAUUAUUAAAAUUUAGAGCUUUAUUUGCUAUGUUUGCUAUGGUUGCCAUGUCACCGGGGGAUAGCACUUUCCAUAGAAUAUAAAGAAAUAAAUAGGAUCUUCGUCCAGUGUGAAUUGGAUUUGCAAUUCUAAUUCAAAUGGAAAGAAAUAUUUUGGACCUCAAAUUCUCAUAGUAUUCUUCCGAAACACUCCAUAACCCCUCUGGCGGAGGGGAAGCAUACUUCCUGGGUUCUCUAAAACAGUUUCUCUCAUUAACAGUUGAUCCUCUUCAGGAGUCACAGAUUUUUAUUGUCUGAUAGCAUAGCUAUCAGUUCGUAUAUGGAUUCACUACCUCAAAGGUGCCUCCUGUUAGAAAACAUUAGCUUUUUUUCAAGAGCAAUUCUGGAGUAAUCUCUUGUUCAAGCUUAUUCACUUGUUCUAGUAAACAUAAUAAUAGGUAUGAACUGCAAUGGUGGCAUAAAAUCCUUUUAAAUUCCAUCCAUUUAACAGGGGAAAUAGAUGAUUACUCCUGACUAUAACAUAUUACUAAGUGAAAUGAUAGAAACAUCUUAUAUUGUGUAAAAGUAAACACUCCAUCUAUUUCUUACUGUUAAAAAAAAAGUACUGAUGAGAUGUAGCAAAGAUUUCUCAGGAUAAAAAUUAACUUUUUUUGUUAUAAGUGGAUGUGGCAUAAUGUACAUGUAUUCUUGGAAAAAAAUUAAAAGAUCCAGAAAAAGAUACAGGUCAUCAAAAUGUAGUUUUAACAAAUCAUCUUUUUCUGAGUAAUAAAUUAGCUUCAAAUUAACAAUGAGUUUGUAUAAAAUGUAUAAAAAAUAACAUUUAUAUCUUUUUUUUUUUUUUUUUUUUUGAGAUGGAGUUUCCCUCUUGUUGCCCAGGCUGGAGUGCAAUGGUGCAAUCUUGGCUCACCACAACCUCCGCCUCCCAGGUUCAAGCAAUUCUCCUGCCUCAGCCUCCCGAGUAGCUAGGAUUACAGGCAUGCGCCACCACGCCCAGCUAAUUUUGUAUUUUUAGUAGAGACGGGAUUUCUCCAUGUUGGUUAGGCUGGUCUCGAACUCCCGACCUCAGGUGAUCUGCCCGCCUCAGCCUCCCAAAGUGCUGGGAUUACAGGCGUGAGCCACUGUGCCCAGUGAGAAGAUUUAUAGCUUAAUGGAAAGACUUGGAUUCUUUGCUCUUAAUUCAAAAGAGUUUUUGUUUUAUUAGCAUUUACUUUUUGAGAUUUUACAAUAUAUUUGGAACUUCUUUAGGUAGCCAGUGGCAAUCCAAAAUUACAUUUUAAAAUGAAAAAAAGAGAAAACUUUUCAAUUACUAAGGCAGGCAAAGCACUAGGAAAUGAAUAAACUUUACCUUUUAAAAAGGAAUCUGUCAACUGCAAAGUUUGUAUAUCUCAGUGACAUCAAGUGAUUUUUGCACUGUCCCAUUGAAAGCAAAGUUUCCUUUAUUUAUUUAUUUAUUCAUUUAUUUUUGAGACGGAGUCUCGCUCUGUCGCCUAGGCUGGAGUGCAGUGGCGAGAUCUCGGCUCACUGCUAACUCCGCCUCCCGGGUUCACGCCAUUCUCCUGCCUCAGUCUCCAGAGUAGCUGGAACUACAGGCGUCCGUCACCACGCCCGGCUAAUUUUUUGUAUUUUUAGUAGAGACGGAGUUUCACCGUGUUAGCCAGGAUGGUCUCGAUCUCCUGACCUGGUGAUCCAACCGCCUCGGCCUCCCAAAGUGGUGGGAUUACAGGCGUGAGCCACCGCGCCCGGCCACAAAGUUUUCUUUUAAACAAAACAUGGAAAAGUUCUUGCUUGAACUUUCACACUGAUUAAUCAAAGUAACAAAUCUCUACAUCAUUAAGAGAACUUUUGAUUUGUUUCAUUAUAGAGAAAGUCUCAAAGAAUUCCAUUACCCUUAGACACAACUAAUUCAUUCCUCAGAAUAACAAAGGUAUUAAAGAAAAAUCACUUGACAGAUGAGGAGGAAAAGUAGCUCUUAAAUGUUAAAUAAAGAUGUGGCUUCUAUAUUUAAUUAAAAAAUAAGGUAUAAAUUAACAACACAAUCUUCUCAGGAGUUGUAAACUAGAAAAGUAUCAGAAUUAGUGAAAAUCUUCCCUUAAGUAAAACUGUUCUUACUUGUAUUUUCUGCAUUAUUUGUGACCUCUGGCCAUUUUUAAUUUGUCAUAAUAAACUCAUUUCUGGUUAGAUAAUAAGUUAUAAUCUCAACAAAUCAGAACAACUGAGAUACAAGUAUAGAUAGGGUGCUCUACAAAAUAAUAAAAGGAGGACAACUCUAAUUCAGGAUUCCUAUUUAGUUAGUAACAGGGUCUCCAUCUCAUUAUCCCUCGCUGAAGUGAGAACUAUCUUUAUCCCAAAAUAAUACAUUAUUAUAGAAAAAAUUCCAAGGAUAUAAGAAUCAUUUUUCAUAUAUUCCAUUCAAUUUGUAUAUUUAGGUAUUAGUAACUGAGGAUAGAUAUCUUUGUUUCAUGAGUUCAAUAUGAGCUUACAUGAGAAGCAAAUUGAUGUGAACAUUUCUCUACAAGUUUUUCCACAUUUGUAGCUCAUCCUUAGAACAGUCUUAAUUUGGCUCUGUUCUAUAAAGACUCAAUAUCAUUUAAUUUUUCAAAAUCAUGAUAGGGAGAAGAAUGCUAAUUUGUAAAGAUAGGCAAACACUACACUUUUAAGAUUUUUACCGUAAGUAAAAUGUCCUCUUCCACUGCUUUUAUAAUUAAAAAUCUCUUUCCUACCUUUAGUAAUUUGUAGGAUGAACUGUAUGCAUUUAGAUAGAAAUUGCUUUUGUUAAAUUUACAUUUAAACACAUCUUCAUUCACUUAGAGAAGCCAUAAUAUAAUUCUUCAUAUUAGUUUAUUUUUCAAAGUAGUAACUUUUGCUAUCUUUAGAAUUCUCAUCUACCCAGUAAUAUAAUUAUUAAAGUCAUGAGGAAGUUUUUCUUUGACUGUGCAUGCUUUAUUUAUUACCAUAUUGUUUUUGUCUUCAGAAUAAGUCUGCUCAAAAUUGUAGCCUUUAGAAGCUCUAUAACAAAAAUCAAUGGCCAAUAACUUGCUAACAAACUUGUAACUGAACAAGCUAUUUUUUUCUGUCAAUGUGAUUGAUAUGCUCAUUGUUAAAUUUAACUUGUUUAAAUAUCCAUUGGUAUAUUAUCAAGAGCUAUUACUGCAAUAACCUCAAAGUAUCUUUAAGACAAUGCUGAAUAUCAUACAUAGUUAAUAAACAAUGAUUGGAGCUUUUCAAAAUUGCUGCUCUGCAUGGAAAGUAAGGUUUAAUGUGUAUAAAUGUUUGUCAUUGAAGUUUGGAAUUUAUUUUAAUGUACUCUUUCUUCCCAUGCUAGAUAUGUCUUCAAAGAAAAAUGUAUUAAUAUAUUCAUACUAUGCAAAAAUAUCAUUUUAUUCUUACCAAAAAAAUGUAGCUUUGAUAAAAUUUUAUGGUUUUUAGGCCUCUUAGAGUAAAAAAAAUCAAAAUGUGAAAUGGGAGCAUUUUGGGGAGCGAGCAGGACACAAUAUCUGAGCAGUGUUAACAAAUAUGAACAUGAGUAACAUUUGAUGUAAAGAUUAUGGUGUGUGCUUGAUUUUGGAUACAUUAUUAUUCAUUUUGUUAGUCACAUUCCACCUUGGAUUGUGACAUUGAAAAACAUUGAAUAUAUACAGGAUAUAAAUAUCUUUGGGAUAUUUUACAUAAUCAUACUUAUUUUUAAUUUUGUGUACAGUGAAAACUUUGACAGUUUAAUUUUGAAUUUUGAAGGAAUAAUUUUUAACAGUCUUUGUUUCUUAAAAUGUUAAUUAUGGUAUACGUGCUAUAGUAACCUCAUUUUUUAAAAAAAUCAGAGGCAAAGCAAGAAUGCAGAACAUGGCAACAGACUAAGUUCCACUAAAAUUAAGGAAAACACUAAAAGGUAAUACAGUACAAAGAGGAGUUUGUUUUAAAAUUGUUACUUACCUCAUUUUAAAAACUGUUAGAAAAGAGUGAAUAAAAAGUAUGUCACAGUACUCUUACUGGUAAUUUUGAAACUAAAGUGCAUUUCAAGGAUGGGAAUCUCUAAUAUAAAUGAGUACACUAAUAGUUGUUAAAAUAUGUAUUGAUACAUACAAUUAGAAAGAAAUGUCAUCAAAAUAUCAAAAAUAGGAAAAAGUUCAUUUUAAAAAUGUUUUGUAAUGGAACAAGUCAUCAAAAUUCUUAACAUUUCCAUAUUAUUAAUCCUUUGUUUUCCAAGACAUAUAUAAUCAAAGAAUUUGCCAAAAAAUUCAAAUAAUAAUACAUUGAAUAUUGGACUGCCAUAGCACUUUAAACAUAUUAAUAAAUUAUCCCAUGGAUAAUAAAGAGAUUUUUUUCCAGCCAUCAUUAAAUAUAAAAAUAGUAUAUAUAAAGAUGCAUAAAAAAGGAACUUACUUGAUACCGUCUUUUAGCAUCAAUUUAUCUUGUUAAGCAGUUAUAUUAAUUUUACACAUACUCUUAAAUGCUUAAAAACAUAGUACUUACAUAUUAAUUUUAUGUGAUAUAAUAUGUUUUGAUCUCUAAAUGCUUACAUUCUUUCAAGAAGAUUGCCUUCUCUUUCCAGUUGUUUUAAGUAUUUUAAAAAAGAGCCAUUGUAUUUUUUAUAUUUCCAUUCAGUCUCAUUAUGCUUGAAAGUUUCCAACUCUCAAAUAAGUUGAAACCAAGUGUCAUAGCACAGUGGCUAGAAGUUAUUCUUUUUGAAGUUAUUCUUCUUUUAUUUAAUAUUAGUCUGAUAUCCCCUAAAAUUUGCUAGAGAAAGCAAACUCUUCUCAUGAAUGGAAAUACAAAAUGAAAAUUCUCCACUGGAUGUUAUAAAUUCAAAAAAAGAACAUAUAUUUUUUAUAGUUACUUCUCACUACUUACUGCUUAUUCAGUUUGUAAAAUCUUACCAAGUAGGAUACUUCAAACAAGAGUGAAAAGCUACUCCAUUUACGUGUAAUCUGCUUAUUUUCUUCAGAGUUUCCAAAAACCUUUGAGAAAACAAAAUAAUCGUUUUCCCUACCUUACAACCUUGAUCACUCUACCAUUAAAUGCAAUAAUAAGGUAUCUAUAAUAUAACAAUCAAAAAUAUCAGUCAAAGCUUAGUGUUUACCUCUUUAAACUAUAUAACAAAUAUAACCGUAGCAACAACAAAUUAAAGGAGAUCAUGUCUCCUUACUGGUCCAAAAUUGUAUAAUUCCUAAAUUUUCAUAUAUAUACAUAUACUGACAUACCUUUAAAAUAUAUUUAUCUGUAAGUCCAUUCACUCCAUUCAACUGUUUAUUGAACACUACCAUGUACCAUUGUCCUGUUCGAAGCACUGAGGAUACAUGGUGACCAAGACAAGCAAAGUCCCUGUCUCAUGGAAUUGACCUUCUAGUGAUAAAGACACACAAUGAAGAAAUAGUGAUGUGCUGUGCUUAUAAUUAAAAAUGUUACAUAGCAUGACUGUGGCUCCUUUAAGCGGUAGAGGAAAUCUUCCCCCAAGGACAUGCCAUUUAAACUGAUAUCUGAAAAGCAUGAAGGAAGCAUCCAUGAGAAGAUAUGGGGGAAGAGCAUUACAAGCAGAGGGAAAAUUUAAUGAAUGAAAUUACAAGCAGAGGGGGAUAGUUAAUGAAUGAAAAUUUGGAGUGUUGGAGAGUAGAGAACAGUGUUCUUGGUACACUGAAAUGAGGCAAAAAGAGGAGAAGGUAUACGCAUGAGGCUACUGGAGUAAUUCCAGCAAAAACGUGGUGGAUUCACUACUUCAAGAUUUGGAAGGCAUCAGUAUAUAUAUGCUAUUUAAAGUUUGGAAAUCACCUAGGAAAAGCCUGUGGAGGUAGGCCUAGGAUUGCACUAUAUGCUAUUCCAAUGUUUAAUAGGCAGAUAAUUAGAAUUAAACAGAAGAAAUGGAGUAUAAAGUAAGCUAGAGAAAAAGGAAAUGCAGUUGCUCAUCUGGAUUAAAUGCUUUUAAGAAGUCAAGAUUAGAACAAAGACAUGUCCAUGGGAAUUAGCAACAUGGAAGUUGUUGUUGUUGAUGACCUUCACAAGGUCAUCAACUAUGAAAAUAGUGGAGUCAACUAUCAACUAUGAAAUAGUGGAGUCAAAUCCCAACUGACAUGGAUUAAGGCGAGAUGUAAAGGAAGGAGGUGAAAUCACUAUCUAUAAACAACUCUCUCAAAAAGCUUUGAUGUAAAGGGAGCAAGAGAAAUAGGAUAAUAGCUGGAGAAAGGAAGUCAAGGAAUUGUCUUGUUUUUUAAGGAUGCUACAGCAUAUUUAUCUACUAAUGAAAAUGACUUGGCAGACAGGGGAAAACUGAUUAUGCAAGAGAGAUGAUAAUUGUAACAAAGGCCUUGAGAGAUAGAGGGGUUGCGAUUUAAAGCAUAAGUAGGGAGGUUAAUUUUUGAUAGGUGCCGGAAUAUAGAACUCCAAUGAAAGGAAGGCAGAAUGUGUAAUGUGCAAAUAGGUUGGUAUAUUUGUGGUAGAAAGGGAAGGAUGUCACUACGUAAGUUUUUUUUUAAUUUUACCAAGAAUGAGAUAAAAGCCAAUAUGCAGGAUGGGAAGGACGUAUAGGUUGGAAGAGACAUAUGUAAGUAGUUGGAUAGUAGGAAAGUGAAUAUAUAUUUGAUGAAAUAUUUUAAAGGCAUCUUUACUAAAUAUUUUUGAGACAUCUUAUUGGAAGACCCGAAACUUUGAAUUCUGUGGUUUCCAAGGACUCUGGUAAGAGUCCUUUCCAUAAUGUAGAGAUUGAGAACUUCUCAAUGCCAUAAAUACUGUUUUCCUUAUUUUCAUCUAUUACAGAUUAAAAGGCAGAAACAUUUUGUAGCUAAUCUGUUAUAAUGCAAAGCCUAUCAAACUUAAAAUUAGCUUAAUCCUGAAAGAUGUAUAUUGCAUAAUCAACCUGUCACUUUUUUCAAACACGAUUUGGGAGGGUAUUGAGGUCCCAUGUAAAUUUUAAAAUAAAAGACAAACAGGAACUAAUCUUUUAGUAAAAAUUAUUUUGUUUUCAUAUAGGAAAACAAUGCCUUCUGUCAUUUACGGAAAACACAUGGGCAAUAUGGUUGGUUGUUCAUUGUGCCCCUCUAUCCUAUAGGAAGAAUGUGAUCUUUUAAUUGUGCUUGGUGCUUUGUUUCUGGAGAUAUAUAUAUAUAUAUUAUAUAUAUGUAUAUAUACCAUAUGUAUAUAUACAUAUGUAUGUGUGUAUGUGUGUAUAUAUAUCUCUCUAGGUUGUAUGUAAUUCAAUAUGUUGGAAUUUAAAGAUGCAUUAUUAUUUGGAUUUGAUGUGAAAUUAGAUUGUGAAUAAUGGAGAUUGCUCUCCAUUUUUUGCUGUUCUAGCAUAGCCAAAAAUAUAAAGAUAUAGAUGUACAUAUACAUAUGUAUUUGAUUAAACACUUUAAAUUUUAAAUGGCCGCAUCAAAUUUUAAAUGGUAGAUGAUAUCAACAAUUGCAGUGCACUCAAAAUGUUAUAAAAUCUUUGUAGCACAAAUCCUGAAGUAUAUGCAAACUAAAUAGCAUAUUUAUAUAAAAUACCUAGAUAACAUGUCUAGGUUGAGAUAUUUAAUCCCUCAUAGAGCUAUAUUUGACUAAUAAAAAACGACAGCUAAAAAUAAUUUCCCUCCCUAUAAGUACAAAUAUGAUUUUUAAAGCAUCAUUGUAACUUGUCAUGAAGCUAUUUAUUAUUAAUUAAGGAUUUAACUCUGUACCCAUCUGCUCUUACAAAAGGGGAAAAAGAUUUAUCUAUGAGAAUAGGGAAGUAUAGCACUGUUUUAUGUUUUUCUCUUUAGUAUUCUGUCACCAUUUAAAGCUUCAAUAUAUGCCUUCCACUCAGGUUCCUGACACAGCCUACAUUCUCUUUUCUGGUUAUAAUCACAAUAUGGUAGAGCUAUAAACAAGGUAAAAAGGUGUUAACAAUUGAACUGCAAUCCUACCUAUUAUCUACUUUACUAUAGCAGUGAAGUAGUCCAGACUUAUUUGAAGGUGGUACUAUUUUUAUCUUACAAAAAUCUACUAUAAUAUUAAUAACUUUCCAUGUAAAUUUUCAUGUGCUGGCAUGCUUACAAGUUAAUAGUGUUAUAGAAUGCUCAGCUCUCAAUAUGAGGGGUUGUUUGUGGUGAAUUGCAUAACAUAUGUCAUCUAUUUGCUGAAAGAAUAUGCUGUUUAGCAAACUACCUGCUGAGCAACAUAAUAAGAUUUUUGUACAAGGUACAAAUUACUAAUUAUUGUAUUUUAUUUUUCUAUGAUUUCCUAAGAGGCAUUAUCAGGGUCUUACAGAUGGAGUAAGCCUGUUUAUUAAAAUAUCUAUUGGCAAAUAAAAGUUACAGCUUUGGUGGUUGAA